AAACAGUCGGGAAGAAGCACCGUGGCUGCUAUUAUCUGCUCUCCGCGCCUGACCCCUCCCAGGACUCGUGAUGCCAAGGCCGCUGCGAGCGGCUACGAAGAGUCGGGGUUGAGCCCCAGCUGAGCCGAGGGCUCGCACUCUUCUGGUCUCCCAGGCCCAACCCACCUGAAGAAAUGAGUGGUGGAUUGGCUCCAAGUAAGAGCACAGUGUAUGUAUCCAACUUGCCUUUUUCCCUGACAAACAAUGACUUGUACCGGAUAUUUUCCAAGUAUGGCAAAGUUGUAAAGGUUACCAUCAUGAAAGAUAAAGAUACCAGGAAGAGUAAAGGGGUUGCAUUUAUUUUAUUUUUGGAUAAAGACUCUGCACAAAACUGUACCAGGGCAAUAAACAACAAACAGUUAUUUGGUAGAGUGAUAAAAGCAAGCAUUGCUAUUGACAAUGGAAGAGCAGCUGAGUUCAUCCGAAGGCGAAACUACUUUGAUAAAUCUAAGUGUUAUGAAUGUGGGGAAAGUGGACACUUAAGUUAUGCCUGUCCGAAAAAUAUGCUCGGAGAACGUGAGCCUCCAAAGAAGAAAGAAAAAAAGAAAAAAAAGAAAGCUCCUGAACCAGAAGAAGAAAUUGAGGAAGUAGAAGAAAGUGAAGAUGAAGGGGAGGAUCCUGCUCUUGACAGCCUCAGUCAGGCCAUAGCAUUCCAGCAAGCCAAAAUUGAAGAAGAACAAAAAAAAUGGAAACCCAGUUCAGGAGUCCCCUCAACAUCAGAUGAUUCAAGACGCCCAAGGAUAAAGAAAAGCACAUAUUUCAGUGAUGAGGAAGAACUUAGUGAUUAAAAUCUUGCCCCAGCACAGUAAUAAAAAUCAAGAUUUGUUAGUAACAAUCUUGAAGAGCUAAUUUUAAUAAAAAUAAGAAAAAUUAAUACUAUCAUGUUAAUACUAUUAUUGUCAUCCCAAGAAAAAAGAUAUUUUAAAAAUUUAUUUGAAAAGUUCAUUAUAAGGGCUUUAUUCAUGCCUGAUUUGUUUACAUGAGGACUUCUGAAAUUAAUCCUUAAAACAAACUUCCUGAAGACCGAAAAGUUGAAUGAUUUAUUGUUACUUAUAUUAAUAAACUUUUCAAGAGAAUUUUGUCUUUAAAUAUGGGUGUUUUGUCAUCAUAUUUCUUGUAGCUUUAUCCCAAUCUGGAUAAAUUGUAAAUACCUAUAAAAUAAAUUAUAAAUACCUAUAAAAUAUAAAGUAACAUAGCUCUAAAAGGCUUAAAAUCAAACACAGGUGUUAUUUGUCUGCCCUACCCAUAGCACCAAAUUCCAUUCCCUAGAAGAAACUACUUACAUGUGCACACAUGUAGCUAAAUAAAGUACAUAUAUUUCAGUCACUUAAUAAAAGAAUAAAGGAGAAUUAUUCAAUCUCUUAUACUUCUCCUACCUUCCUCAAUAUUCCCAAUGUGGCUGUAUUAAAAAUUUGGGGGAAUCCAUAUAUAUCUUUUUUAAUAACCAAGUAAAUACUUUUCAUUUCUGAGCCAAGGAAUAUGCUAUGAUUACGUUUUUUCCUAGAGUUAAUAAUUGUCUAUUUUUUUUCCAUGUAUUGUCUUUGUAUUUAUGACUAAAUCUUCCCAUUCUGUCUGCAGGUGGGUAUAUGGUAAUGGGAUUAGAGAGCCUUUAAUUUUCUGCUUUGUAUAUUUCUAUAUUGUUUAACUUUGUAAGAAUGCCCAUUACUUUUUUAACUAGUAAAAGCAAUAGAAAUAAGUUAAUACUAUCAUAGUAAUAUUAUUAUUGUCAUCCCAAGAAAAAAUAUAUUAAAAAGAUAUUUGAAAUUUCA